GCGGGGCGGGCGGAGGUGACGCUCGGUCGGCGCGCCCGGGAAGGGAUCGUCAGGUUUUCCCUGAGAGGCUGCGGCGCUGCUGCCAGCCCUGUUCUGUUGAGAAUCUCUCCUACCCGCAUUCAAGUGCUCUCUCUAAAGACCUCGCUCACCCCGCCUGCUCCUGCGGAGUGACUGCCGCAGCGGGGCCGGAAGACAGGUGCGCCCCAGCCUCGCCAGCUCUGGCCCUGGCCUCCGGGGAACUCGGCGCCUCCCUCGUCACCGUCGGUGGCGGUUAAAACUGGCCUCUACGCUUCUGCUUCAAUCUCCAAUUUGGCAUGCAAAGCACACCUUUUUGUGGUUUUUGCAGUUUGGGGAAGAUGAUAACAGCUAAGCCAGGGAAAACACCGAUUCAGGUAUUACACGAAUACGGCAUGAAGACCAAGAACAUCCCAGUUUAUGAAUGUGAAAGAUCUGAUGUGCAAAUACACGUGCCCACUUUCACCUUCAGAGUAACCGUUGGUGACAUAACCUGCACAGGUGAAGGUACAAGUAAGAAGCUGGCGAAACAUAGAGCUGCAGAGGCUGCCAUAAACAUUUUGAAAGCCAAUGCAAGUAUUUGCUUUGCAGUUCCUGACCCCUUAAUGCCUGACCCUUCCAAGCAACCAAAGAACCAGCUUAAUCCUAUUGGUUCAUUACAGGAAUUGGCUAUUCAUCAUGGCUGGAGACUUCCUGAAUAUACCCUUUCCCAGGAGGGAGGACCUGCUCAUAAGAGAGAAUAUACUACAAUUUGCAGGCUAGAGUCAUUUAUGGAAACUGGAAAGGGGGCAUCAAAAAAGCAAGCCAAAAGGAAUGCUGCUGAGAAAUUUCUUGCCAAAUUUAGUAAUAUUUCUCCAGAGAACCACAUUUCUUUAACAAAUGUAGUAGGACAUUCUUUAGGAUGUACUUGGCAUUCCUUGAGGAAUUCUCCUGGUGAAAAGAUCAACUUACUGAAAAGAAGCCUCCUUAGUAUUCCAAAUACAGAUUACAUCCAGCUGCUUAGUGAAAUUGCCAAGGAACAAGGUUUUAAUAUAACAUAUUUGGAUAUAGAUGAACUGAGCGCCAAUGGACAAUAUCAAUGUCUUGCUGAACUGUCCACCAGCCCCAUCACAGUCUGUCAUGGCUCCGGUAUCUCCUGUGGCAAUGCACAAAGUGAUGCAGCUCACAAUGCUUUGCAGUAUUUAAAGAUAAUAGCAGAAAGAAAGUAAAUCUGGAGCAACUUAAAAAAUCUUUCAGUAGCACAUAAAAAGUUCCCCUCUGGCCCCUUCCCAAGUAAAACUUUUACCGUAGUGUUUAUGUCUUGUUUCUAAAUCUCUUCAUAGAUUCCAUCAACACUCCAGAUUUAAUUAUCUCCUCAUAGUUGUUAUUAAGCUCUUUUUAAUGGCUUCAACUUUGUAUCAGUAUACUGUAUUUAUAAACUUUGUACCACAAGAGAGAGUGUAGCACCCAUUUUACAGUGCCAUGCACAUCAGAGAAAGAAACUGCAUGUUUGUUGUUGAUGAUGAAAUAAAAAUGCUAGCGACAGUCUUUCUUACUGGUGCUUAAGCUCUUCUUUGCACAAAGCUUUAUAAAGGGAAUUCAAAGGAAGCCCUUUAGAAUUAGAGUCUUGAGGGACAGCACUAACAGGCCUUUAUUAAGUAUGAUUGAUUGUUAAAUUUCAGGGAACAUGAUUGGUCUGCUGUGUAUUUGAAUUCAUGUAACAAAGAACUGUUACGAUGGGAUUCUGCUCAUUUUAUUAAAAAGCUACUGACUUGACUGUCAUCCUGUUCUUGUUAGCCAUUGUGAAUAAGAUUUUAAUGUUGAUAAUUCUGUUAUUUACAUAUCUCUAAUUUACUUUGAAAUUCAAAGGUGAAAAUAAAAAAUGAUGGCCUAAGUAAAAUUUACAAACAUA